AGUCUCCCUGCUCUCCGUGGUCCCGGCUCGCGUGUAGCGGCGGCGGCGGCGUCUCCGUGAGGAGGCGCGCGGGGCCAUGACGUCAGCGUCCACAAAGGUCGGAGAGAUCUUCUCGGCGGCCGGCGCCGCCUUCACGAAGCUCGGGGAGCUGACGAUGCAGCUGCAUCCCGUGGCCGACUCUUCUCCUGCGGGUGCGAAGUGGACGGAGACGGAAAUAGAGAUGCUGAGGGCUGCUGUGAAGCGAUUUGGGGACGAUCUUAAUCACAUCAGCUGUGUCAUCAAGGAACGGACAGUGGCCCAGAUAAAGGCCACUGUGAAACGCAAGGUAUAUGAAGAUUCUGGCAUCCCCCUUCCAGCUGAGUCACCCAAGAAAGGGCCCAAGAAGGUGGCAUCUGGUGUCUUGUCACCUCCUCCAGCUGCCCCUCCUCCCAGCAGCUCCAGUGUCCCUGAGGCCGGGGGUCCCCCCAUAAAGAAACAGAAGGCUGAUGUGACACUCAGUGCUCUGAACGACUCCGAUGCCAACAGUGACGUGGUGGAUAUUGAAGGGCUAGGAGAAACUCCUCCAGCUAAGAAACUCAACUUCGACCAGGACAGCCUGACCCUGGAUUCUGGCCUUCUCAUGACCUCUGCUGAUCCUCCUCUCCUCUCCUGCUGAGCCUUCCACCUCUGACCUCUCACUGUUCAUGCCGGACCUGUGGAUCUCCUGGGACUCCGAGCAAGGCCUGCACGAGAGAGGGCUGAAAGGCUGCUGGGGCUGCCACCUCGCUAUUCCCGCAUAAGCAUCUGCCCCCAACCCCUUUGACCUUCAUCUGAUGGACAUUUUUAUACAGAAAACAAUAAAGAUUUCCCUCUCA